AGAACGUCCUUCUCCCUCAGCUGGAGGGAGCAUGGCAGUGAGCCAAGGAGACGGGACCCUCUGCUUUGUCCUCCUGCUGUGCUGUUGGCAAGAAACUGAGCUCCGGCCGAGAACCGUGAUUCCAGAUGGUGAAACCAAGGGAAAGUAACUGCACAUGAUCACAAGGUUAAGCUCUUAAGGACACAAAACAAGACAGAAAAAUUUCAUCCAGUAUUGGUUUCAGGGACCCACAGCAAAGUUUGUAACUGACCAGCCUGCCAGUCUGGCUUGAAAAGCAGGCUUGAAAGUUCACCUACUGAAAUACCAUUCAGUUCAAAACAGGAGGAUAUGUCUGAAUUAUUAGAUGAAAUUCUGGUCCAGGAGAUUUUAGAUCUGAAUAAAACAACACCGAGCGAAAUGCCAAGUACAGCAUCAACAUUAUCAACACCGUUACAUGCUGGUAUUGAUGAGAAUUAUCAAGCUGGUGGUUCUGAGAAUUACCAUGAAUUAUUAGAGAAUUUACAAUUCUCUCCUGGCAUUGAGGUCAAAAUUUCCAAUGAUGAAGCCAAUGCUAAUGCAAAUCUCCAUGGCGAUCCUUCUGAGAAUUAUCGUGGGCCACAGGUGUCUCCUGGCAGUGAGAAGAGUGUUUCCAGUAAAGCAGACGGAAUCUCUCUCCACACUGAGCUGCCUGGAGUUGGAAGAGGAGUGAUACCGGCACUCUCAUGGCCGCCACAGCUGGCACCAAUGCUGGGUCUCACCCAAAGUCCCACAGCUGCCCAGACAAGCACAGUACCAGAGCUCAUCCAAGAAAAGAAUUCAAAGAACACUCAGUAUGAAAAUCUAUCCAUUCUGGACCAAAUCCUUCAAAAUAUUGGAAGAUCUUCAGGAAACAUUUUCCAUAAAGAGCAGCAGAGGACCAGCGCACAGAGGAGGAGCCAAGGCAGUCAGUGAGGCCGCAGCCCCAGACCCCCUGCGCAGGAGAGGAGCCUGCUAGAACCCCCACCCACCAGCCUCCGGAACAGGGCACUUGUGUGCACACGCCCACGUUCUCUGAACCAUUCCACAUAAAGGAAAAUCGUUUAUUCACACGA